CCUGUGGCCGCUGCACAUCGUCCUGUGGACGCGUAUCGCCAGCACGAUCCCACCGCACGUUCAGAAGUCGGGUGAGUGGUCCCCAGCCCGGGCUCGGCGGGGCGCCGGGGGUCUUCCUGGGGUCCCCGCCUCUCCGCUGCGCUUGACAGUCGGGCCCGGCAACCCGGCCCCCGGGCGGAAACGAGGAAAGUUUCCCCCGCGACACUCACGCAGCCCGACUCCCGUAGCUGCAGGGAUUGUGAGUUUUUCUUGAAAAAGAGAAGGAAAGUUCAGUUGCAAGGGGCGCGGGGCACGUUUGGUCCCCUUUGUGCGAGCAGGAAAGGCGUUGUGUUGGCCGCGUUCGAGGCGAGCCCCCACCCCCGGAAAGGGAAGUUUGAGAAGUUGGUUAUCUGAAGGCGGCCGGGGAGCAGCGGCCCGGAGCGGCAGCCUGAGCUGCCAAAGCAGCCAGCGCACCUGGGCCACUCCGCCCAUGGCGAUGCCGCGUGCCCACCCAGCUCUUUCUGAGCCACCCGUUCAAAAGGCCAGCUCCUCAGUCCUUAGCUCCUGGAGACGGCCACGCUUUCCCUCAGGCCGGCUUCUUGGCCCGGAGUUUUUGGAAACAAGUUUCAAGAAAAUAAUCGAUUUCCAAAAGAAAGUUAGCUGGCUCCACUGACGCCUUGGCAUGGAUGGAUAGGGAGUGGAGAUGCUCAGGUGAAACCGAGAAUCCCUCACUGAAUGCCUACUGGGUGCUAGAGGCUGUAGAUUUUGCCUGGAACAAGAUAGUCCUGUCUUCAGGGAGUUGAUGGUUCUAUGCAAUUAUCGUUUGUUGGAAACCGAAGGGUUAAAAUCCUAACUAGGCUACCCACCUGAUCGCUGUCUCUGAAGGUUUUUAAGGAAAAAAUAAAAAUAAAAAAAUAUAUAUAUAUAUUAUAUAUAUAUAAAUAUAUAUAUAAUUAUAUAUAUAAAUAUAUAUAAUAUUAAUAUAUAUAUGCAUGCAGGAAUGGGGGUUCUUAACUAUUUGUUAUGGAAAGUGUAAAACCUCUGAGACUUCAAAAGUUAGAUUUUUUUUUUUUGGAGACGGAGUCUCGCUCUGUCACCAGGCUGGAGUGCAGUGGCGCAAUCUCGGCUCACUGCAACUUUGCCUCUGGGUUCAAGCGAUUCUCCUGCCUUAGCCUCCCGAGUAGCUGGGAUUACAGGCGCGUGCCACCACGCCCAGCUAAUUUUUGUAUUUUUAGUAGAGACGGGGUUUCACCAUAUUGGCCAGGGUGGUCUCGAUCUCUUGACCUCGUGAUCCGCCCACCUUGGCCUCCCAAAGUGCUGGGAUUACAGGCGUGAGCCACCGCGCCCGGCCAAAAGUUAGACUUUUUGCAGCUAUGAUCCAAAUAACAGUAUCUGCAGCUGUGGUCUGGGUAACCGAGUAUUUGGGCAAGUCAUAGAGCUUUUUCUGGGCCUUAGUUUCCUCAUCUGUAAAAUGGCCAGCUUGAAUCUGGGUAAUUUUACAUCAUCUUCAUGUUUAACAUCUUACGUAUCGUGCCCCUCCCCUCCUUUCCCCUGGCUCUUCUGGUGACUUGGAGAUGACCCAUGUAGACUUUGGAUGAAAUGUAGAGGAGUUGACAGUCCACAUCACCCGGAGGCACUCAUUUUAUUUAUCCAGGGACAUGGGCAGAUUUACCUUUAGGUUUGUCUAGAAAAAAUGCGCAUCACGGUCAGUUGUAAAUUUUAGAGUGUUUGAAGUGGAUUGGGAACUUUUUAAAAAUUAUGGCAUACAUUGAAGGUGGCAUGGAGAUGGAAGCUUUUAAUCAAAUUAGGAAGAGGCACUAUUGCAAGCAAAAAGUCUUGACACACAUUUGAGUCCUAUGGUUUUAAUAAAAUCUUAGUGUUUCGUUCUUGGCGUUUUUCCUGCAUUGCAGUACCAGAAUGUUCAAUUGUCUCUCAUUUUCCUCCAGACUUUUAAAACCUAAGUGACAUUUUGCUAAUAAAUAUUUAAAAUGGCACCCUUAAUUUUCUGUGGAUGUUAAAAAUCAUUACAACUUUUGUUCCAGAUUAUAAAAGAAGGAAAUUAGCAGGCCCUGAUGUUGUUAGUUAGGUUCUGUUUACAAGGAUAAGGUUUAUGAUUUGCAAAUUCCAGACCCAAUAGUUCACGAGUCACUUUCAUUUCAUCAAUAUACACACUUUUAAACAAUUAGCUUAAAAACGUGGUGGCUUUUUAUUUGGGUAUUUAGACAGUUUUACAAGGCCCACAGAUUUCAUAUUUUUAUAGAACUGAAGUUUCAAAAUGGUUGAAUUAAUGAAUCAUUUUGAAUUUGUAUUCAUUUGAUUCAAAUUAAAUUUUCAAAGUUGGCCAAUGGUUGAAGACAGAUAUAUUGAAGACGAGAAACCUAAUUCUACUUACAUUUUAAUUUUUCAUGUAAGUAAAUAGUUUCAGAAUUUCUCUAACGUAAUUGGUAAACUGAAAACAUUUUUUCAAAAUAUCUUAAUGCAAGAUAAUAUAUCAGGUAAUGAGAUUGUUUAAUAAACAACAAGCUCCUUUUACGUCACCUAAAAAGGCCCAAAAAUCUGUCUUCUGUUUAGUAGCUUCUGUACUUCUGUUUAGUAGUAUGCAAAGGAUUUAAAUAAAAGAACAAAUUUCACUAAGAAAUAGAAAGUUUUUUUUUCUUCGUUUUUGACUUAAUAGAUUCACUCUUCCUAAAUGAUCAAAAUUAAGAAAUGACUCUUUUGGGGAAAACUGUAAAGUGCACAAUAACUCUUCAGGUCUGAAAAAUAUGACUUUUCAGGUUCCUGGAAGUAGAUAGAUUCUUAUUGAGGACAAAGAAUUUGUAAAAGUGUCAUAGUGAUCAGGUUCUUCACAUCACUUUAAUAACCUGCUUAUUUUGUCAGGGUAAGAGACUAGACAUCAUUAGGCCCCAAAUCUGAUCUUCAGUCUACUCGUGCUUUUUUUCCGCCUCAUAAAAACACAUUUCCACCUUUAGGCCACUCAACAUCUUAUUUUUAAUGAGUUAUGAUUUAUACAAAAUACUAAUCACAUUUUGAACUCAUUGCCUUCUUUUCAAUGUAGCAUUCCCUAAUGAUGACUGUUGUCUAUGUAGUCAACAUAACUACUACAUGUUUUCUACUCAGUUAUGAACAUGACUUUUUAAUUUUUUCAGUAAGGUUAGUUUUUAACUCUGGAUCAAUAAGGCACCUCUGAUAUCAUUGCAAAAACUGGGCAUUUUUUCUUCUACCUUUUCAACCAUAUUUAUUGAGUAUCUCUUGCCAGGCAGGAUGCUCAGACCUGGGAUACCAUCUCAGAUGAAUAAGACAGACCUGGUCUUUGCCAUUGAAUUUAACAGCUGGGAGCAUGUUAUAAGUAAAGAAAAGGAUACGUGUUUUAACUGUUUAUAUUUGAAAGCAUUAUGGAAUACUGGUGUUUUAUUUUCUACACCUCAUUUUCAAAAGCCUCAUUUUUUUUUGUUGUUGUAUGCACUAGGAGGAUGUGCAUGUUGAAUGUUUCCUUCUAGGUCCCAUUGAAUGUAUUUUUGAAUCAAUUUGUUGUCUCUUUCCUAUCCCUGCCUUGUCACGGAGCCCCAGUUGGGCAGCCUUUAAUUGCAUUCUCCAUUCCAUAGCCAGCAUGAUGGACCCAAUGCGUUCAUUUAGUGCUCUCUUUGAGGAUAGGCUGGUGGUAGAAGAGUGUAGGGUAUAAACUUUGGAAUCAGGCCGUCCUGGGUUCCAGACCCACUUGCCAUGUACUGGCUGUGUAGCCUGUUGUAGUUGCUUUACCUACUAGUCAUCCCUGGUCUCAUUUGUAAAAUGAGGAUUAUGGAGUUAUGGUGAGGAUUAAAUAAAAUAUUGUUUUAAAGUAUUUAACAUGGUGCCUGCAACAUAGUAAAUGCUCAAUAAAUAUCAGCUUCUGUUAUUACUAUUAACUCCUUAAUUGGGCUUACCAGGGGCCUCUGACCUGGUUCCCAUUUGACUCUGCUGCUUCACAUCCCACCACAGCCCACAUUUUCCCAGUCUAUUUGUGUCACUACACAUACACACAAUGUGAGCAAUUUAGGCAGCUGUUCCUUUGUUCAGGAUGUCUGGAACUCCUGCUACCUGGCUAAUUUUCACUCAUCUUUUAAGACGUAGUUCAAGUGUCAUCUUCUUGAGGAAACCUGCUUUGAAUGUCCCAGUUUGAGGUAAAUGUCUCCUAUGAGAUACAGACCUCUCACUUAGCUGGUAACAAUACCAAGCCAAAGUCAUAUCUUUACGUAACUCUCUUGCCCAUUAUACCUUUAAUCCUCUCAAUCUUAUUCAGUUUUCUAUCUCUGGGAUCUCUGGCAGUGCCUGACACAUCAUUUAGCACCCAGGAAGUGCUGAGCUGAGCCUCCACUUCAUCCUACUGUAUCUAAUGCAACUGAGGUCGAGCAUUUAACUAAGCAGUCACUGUUUGUUAGGUGUUUGGUCCAAAUAGUAAAAUCUUUACUUUCAGUUAGAAUAGUUUUAGUUCUGAUCACAAUAAGUAAUUUGACUGUUUUUGAAGUAUGGAAUUGGUUCUUGUAUUCUCAUGAAAUAUGGAAAAAGAUGUUUCAACUUCUGACAAACAUGAUGGAAAGCUGCUAGAAGUUUUCAUGCAAUUCCUUUAGCCAUAAAUUUUGAAUCAGUGUAGGGCCUUGAAAGCCACUGCAAAAUUUUAAAUAAAGUCACCAGAGGAAUUAUCCAGUAGAUACUGAUUCCUCUUUUUUUUUUUUUUCAUAGAAGGGUGUCGGAAAGAGAAUUUUAUUACGAAUGAAGUGCUAAAAUCUAAAUUUAUUUUUUAAGUUUCUUUUUUCAUUGGGUUUUAUGUUUUGGUUUAUAAGGGUGAAGCAGCGUUGGUUGAAGGGAAGUGUGGUCUUGUAGCCACCACUGCCUACUCUAGAGUAGCGUGGAUAUUAUUUAGGUCUGAUGCAAACCACCAAAGCAGUUUUAAAUAGGGUGCAGGGGAAACAUACUUCCUGGCUACAGCAUGGCAUUAUUUGGCCAAGUUCCACAUAAAAGCAUAACUCUGUUACCUUGUUAGCUUCUACCCUCCAGGUCCUUAUGUACAACUUCAGCAGAUUUAAGUUAUGAUUUUCAGUAGAACAGAUAUGCAUUCGCAGCAAGAAUGCUCACCGCUUCUUUUGCACUCUCUACUUUCCUGGUAAUAUUUUGCUCCACAGGUACUUGUUGCUUGUGACUGAGGCAAGAUAAUGACUCAUACUUCUUUGCUUGGCAUGCCAAAGGGUUUGGAAUGCUGGACAGGCAAAUUGUCUCAUCUCAGGGAGAAGGAAGAGAAAGACAAUUAACAUUUGAGAACCUACCCUGAGACAGCCACUUGAUAUUAUGUAUCUCAUUUAAUCCUAGGAAGAAAUCUCCAAGAUAAGUUUUAUUAUCUUUAUUUUAUGGAUGGAAAGAUGGAUCCUGCUCAGGGUCUCUCUGGAGUUUUGCCUGGGUGCAUGUAUGAGUGUGUGGCCCAAGCUUCUUGUGCUUGCAUGCUGCUAGGUUCUUUCGUGUGGUCUCUAUGUGUGUAUGCGUGUGUUGGGAGGGAGGCUGAAGAGGGGUGAAUGGAUAUCAGAUUUGAGAGAGGGGAAGCUUACCAUCUAAUGUCAUCAGUUCAGUGCUCCUGAUUUAAUUGAUUUGGUUUGCUUGCAUUAUCUGCCUCCUUCCUGACUACAUUUGUACCACAGAAAAUCAAGAUAAGGCAGAGUUUCUUUGCAUAAGGAAACUCUACAGCCCACAGUUUGACAAUGGUGUCUUAGUGGUAGGACUCAUGGUGGGUGACCUGUGGUUUGGCCACUUAUAGCAGUUGGACAUACCCCAUUUGCAAAGAUGUGUAUUGUAAACCCCAAAUUUUGAGUGUGUAGGACAAUCAUUUGUGUACAAUCGUGUACAACUGCUGAUGAGGGCAAGAAGAGCCGACUUUAUCCAACAUAACAAAGAAGAAGGGGACAGUUUGACUUUUGAAGGGGACAAUUUGAAAACUUAUAGGAGGUUAAGAUUCUCUUCCUCACCCAUUACAUCAGGAGUACUUCUGCCUUUUACUUGCCACAGUCAGCUUUCUAGGUCUUAGCACCCAACAAGUAGCAACUAUCCUCUUGGGUGUAGUCAGUUUAGUCUACUUAUGGCCUCCUGCUUAGACUCUUAAGGGUUCCCUAGCAUCUGUGUUUUGUUUGUAGGUUUGAAGCUAUCAUUAUUAGAUGAGAUUUAGCUUCAGGGCCCGUACCUAUGACUGGGGAGAUUCUAUCUGGGAAAGGUCAAGACAUGCAGCUCUUUUUUUUUUUUUUUUUUCUUCUCUUUUCUGAGGGAAUAUUUUCCUCCAAUUUUUUUCAGCUCUACAACUAAAAUAUAGACCUAGUAUAUGAACACAACUGGCCUCUGUCCUGGGCCUUAGAUGGUACUCUGCUGUCAUUCUUCUCUGGUCAGAGCCAUGCCUAUGGGGUGAGGUGACUUUUGGGCCUUCCAGUCUUACUCUCUUUUCAUUUUUAGACCAUGAUUUGGUUAUGUGGGAACCCACAUUCGCUGUCCAGAAGGCCCUGAACUGGUAUCUGCAGUUUGCAUGGAUCCUUGAAGCCAUCUUCCUGAAGGCUGUCAUUGCUACUGGUUGUGCAAUCUCUGCACGAGGGUUGUUUAAGGGAUAGCUCUGUGUGUGUGUGUGUCUGUAUGUGAGAGAGAGAGAGAGAGAGAGAGAGAAAGAGAGAGAGAGACAGAGAGCGAGCUUGGGUGUCCACAUAUCACAAGGCCCCUCUUGAUGUAGGAUGGAGCAGGCAGGGGGGAGGAAGGCAAAUUGAUUACCAGGGCUCAGGAUGAUGUCUCUCUUUAAACCACCCAUUUCUGUGGAAGGACUAUGAACAUUGUAGGAGUUCUAAAGUUGUACCUGGUCUUCCAAGACAUUGAAAAGAUAUAUUUGUCAGUCUAGGUAGAAGGAUAACACCUAUUUUAUUGAGCAGUUUGCUAGCUUGAUUUGUAACUUUAAAUGUUUUGACUUAUGGUACAUGGGCCUCUAUUUGCUCACUUGCCUUGGGCCUUCCCAUGUUGGGGGUGGAUCUGCAGCAGCAACAUUCCUUUGCAGAGAUGUUGGGUAGAAAUAAGUUUUGGUUAAUUGUACCAUUUUUUCCCUGGAAUAGACAACAUUGAACAUUAAAGAAAAAAUGAGUUACUUUGUAGACAUAGUGCUCUAUUUCCUUUGGGAAAUGUAGUUUUUCUUAGUUUGCGUUGUCCUGAAGUGAACUUUAGCUCUAUACUUUUUUUCUUUCCUUUUUUUUUUUUUUUUUUUAGAUUUCCUAGUGCCCUAGUUGCAUUUCUUCUGUGUAUUGAGAGACCACCAGGCGGGCAAGGUGAAGUUUAUCUGAAUGUUUUUUCCUCCUAUUGUAAAUAUUUUAUUUGAACCAAAAAAAGGCUUGGUUCUUCUCAAGCCUCUUUAAAGAAAACAAGGAAAAAGGCUUCUCAGUGCUUUAGAAGAUAUAAGAUUGUCAAAACUUCAUUUUAGAGAACUAGGGAUUUGGUUGAACCAACAUGAAUGCCUUUGAAAGAAGAUAUGGGUUGGGUGCAUAUUUUCAGUAUAUGCUGCAGCAGCUCUUUAUUAAAGUAUAAAUCAUUACGAAGUCUUCAUUUCCUAUGGGGCGAUAACACUGCUGCUUUGUGGAUGACUACCUGUCACGCCCAAAUCCUGCAAACUUUUCUACAUAGGGAAAUGAAAUUGGGCUUAUUUCCCCUGUAGCUUUUCUCAAGAGACUUCAUGGACUAAUUUCCCAAUAAUCAUAGUAGCUACCACUUAUUGAGGUCUUGCUACUGCACGGAUCAUGCUGAGUACUUCAGGUGUAUUAACCCUCAAAACAACUUUAGAAGUUAAUAACGACAUGAUAGUCACUGACAACAACGGUGCAGUCAAGUUUCCACAACUGUGUAAAUUUUGUGAUGUGAGAUUUUCCACCUGUGACAACCAGAAAUCCUGCAUGAGCAACUGCAGCAUCACCUCCAUCUGUGAGAAGCCACAGGAAGUCUGUGUGGCUGUAUGGAGAAAGAAUGACGAGAACAUAACACUAGAGACAGUUUGCCAUGACCCCAAGCUCCCCUACCAUGACUUUAUUCUGGAAGAUGCUGCUUCUCCAAAGUGCAUUAUGAAGGAAAAAAAAAAGCCUGGUGAGACUUUCUUCAUGUGUUCCUGUAGCUCUGAUGAGUGCAAUGACAACAUCAUCUUCUCAGAAGAAUAUAACACCAGCAAUCCUGACUUGUUGCUAGUCAUAUUUCAAGUGACAGGCAUCAGCCUCCUGCCACCACUGGGAGUUGCCAUAUCUGUCAUCAUCAUCUUCUACUGCUACCGCGUUAACCGGCAGCAGAAGCUGAGUUCAACCUGGGAAACCGGCAAGACGCGGAAGCUCAUGGAGUUCAGCGAGCACUGUGCCAUCAUCCUGGAAGAUGACCGCUCUGACAUCAGCUCCACGUGUGCCAACAACAUCAACCACAACACAGAGCUGCUGCCCAUUGAGCUGGACACCCUGGUGGGGAAAGGUCGCUUUGCUGAGGUCUAUAAGGCCAAGCUGAAGCAGAACACUUCAGAGCAGUUUGAGACAGUGGCAGUCAAGAUCUUUCCCUAUGAGGAGUAUGCCUCUUGGAAGACAGAGAAGGACAUCUUCUCAGACAUCAAUCUGAAGCAUGAGAACAUACUCCAGUUCCUGACGGCUGAGGAGCGGAAGACGGAGUUGGGGAAACAAUACUGGCUGAUCACCGCCUUCCACGCCAAGGGCAACCUACAGGAGUACCUGACGCGGCAUGUCAUCAGCUGGGAGGACCUGCGCAAGCUGGGCAGCUCCCUCGCCCGGGGGAUUGCUCACCUCCACAGUGAUCACACUCCAUGUGGGAGGCCCAAGAUGCCCAUCGUGCACAGGGACCUCAAGAGCUCCAAUAUCCUCGUGAAGAACGACCUAACCUGCUGCCUGUGUGACUUUGGGCUUUCCCUGCGUCUGGACCCUACUCUGUCUGUGGAUGACCUGGCUAACAGUGGGCAGGUGGGAACUGCAAGAUACAUGGCUCCAGAAGUCCUAGAAUCCAGGAUGAAUUUGGAGAAUGUUGAGUCCUUCAAGCAGACCGAUGUCUACUCCAUGGCUCUGGUGCUCUGGGAAAUGACAUCUCGCUGUAAUGCAGUGGGAGAAGUAAAAGAUUAUGAGCCUCCAUUUGGUUCCAAGGUGCGGGAGCACCCCUGUGUCGAAAGCAUGAAGGACAACGUGUUGAGAGAUCGAGGGCGACCAGAAAUUCCCAGCUUCUGGCUCAACCACCAGGGCAUCCAGAUGGUGUGUGAGACGUUGACUGAGUGCUGGGACCACGACCCAGAGGCCCGUCUCACAGCCCAGUGUGUGGCAGAACGCUUCAGUGAGCUGGAGCAUCUGGACAGGCUCUCGGGGAGGAGCUGCUCGGAGGAGAAGAUUCCUGAAGACGGCUCCCUAAACACUACCAAAUAGCUCUUCUGGGGCAGGCUGGGCCAUGUCCAAAGAGGCUGCCCCUCUCACCAAAGAACAGAGGCAGCAGGAAGCUGCCCCUGAACUGAUGCUUCCUGGAAAACCAAGGGGGUCACUCCCCUCCCUGUAAGCUGUGGGGAUAAGCAGAAACAACAGCAGCAGGGAGUGGGUGACAUAGAGCAUUCUAUGCCUUUGACAUUGUCAUAGGAUAAGCUGUGUUAGCACUUCCUCAGGAAAUGAGAUUGAUUUUUACAAUAGCCAAUAACAUUUGCACUUUAUUAAUGCCUGUAUAUAAAUAUGAAUAGCUAUGUUUUAUAUAUAUAUAUAUAUAUCUAUAUAUGUCUAUAGCUCUAUAUAUAUAGCCAUACCUUGAAAAGAGACAAGGAAAAACAUCAAAUAUUCCCAGGAAAUUGGUUUUAUUGGAGAACUCCAGAACCAAGCAGAGAAGGAAGGGACCCAUGACAGCAUUAGCAUUUGACAAUCACACAUGCAGUGGUUCUCUGACUGUAAAACAGUGAACUUUGCAUGAGGAAAGAGGCUCCAUGUCUCACAGCCAGCUAUGACCACAUUGCACUUGCUUUUGCAAAAUAAUCAUUCCCUGCCUAGCACUUCUCUUCUGGCCAUGGAACUAAGUACAGUGGCACUGUUUGAGGACCAGUGUUCCCGGGGUUCCUGUGUGCCCUUAUUUCUCCUGGACUUUUCAUUUAAGCUCCAAGCCCCAAAUCUGGGGGGCUAGUUUAGAAACUCUCCCUCAACCUAGUUUAGAAACUCUACCCCAUCUUUAAUACCUUGAAUGUUUUGAACCCCACUUUUUACCUUCAUGGGUUGCAGAAAAAUCAGAACAGAUGUCCCCAUCCAUGCGAUUGCCCCACCAUCUACUAAUGAAAAAUUGUUCUUUUUUUCAUCUUUCCCCUGCACUUAUGUUACUAUUCUCUGCUCCCAGCCUUCAUCCUUUUCUAAAAAGGAGCAAAUUCUCACUCUAGGCUUUAUCGUGUUUACUUUUUCAUUACACUUGACUUGAUUUUCUAGUUUUCUAUACAAACACCAAUGGGUUCCAUCUUUCUGGGCUCCUGAUUGCUCAAGCACAGUUUGGCCUGAUGAAGAGGAUUUCAACUACACAAUACUAUCAUUGUCAGGACUAUGACCUCAGGCACUCUAAACAUAUGUUUUGUUUGGUCAGCACAGCGUUUCAAAAAGUGAAGCCACUUUAUAAAUAUUUGGAGAUUUUGCAGGAAAAUCUGGAUCCCCAGGUAAGGAUAGCAGAUGGUUUUCAGUUAUCUCCAGUCCACGUUCACAAAAUGUGAAGGUGUGGAGACACUUACAAAGCUGCCUCACUUCUCACUGUAAACAUUAGCUCUUUCCACUGCCUACCUGGACCCCAGUCUAGGAAUUAAAUCUGCACCUAACCAAGGUCCCUUGUAAGAAAUGUCCAUUCAAGCAGUCAUUCUCUGGGUAUAUAAUAUGAUUUUGACUACCUUAUCUGGUGUUAAGAUUUGAAGUUGGCCUUUUAUUGGACUAAAGGGGAACUCCUUUAAGGGUCUCAGUUAGCCCAAGUUUCUUUUGCUUAUAUGUUAAUAGUUUUACCCUCUGCAUUGGAGAGAGGAGUGCUUUACUCCAAGAAGCUUUCCUCAUGGUUACCGUUCUCUCCAUCAUGCCAGCCUUCUCAACCUUUGCAGAAAUUACUAGAGAGGAUUUGAAUGUGGGACACAAAGGUCCCAUUUGCAGUUAGAAAAUUUGUGUCCACAAGGACAAGAACAAAGUAUGAGCUUUAAAACUCCAUAGGAAACUUGUUAAUCAACAAAGAAGUGUUAAUGCUGCAAGUAAUCUCUUUUUUAAAACUUUUUGAAGCUACUUAUUUUCAGCCAAAUAGGAAUAUUAGAGAGGGACUGGUAGUGAGAAUAUCAGCUCUGUUUGGAUGGUGGAAGGUCUCAUUUUAUUGAGAUUUUUAAGAUACAUGCAAAGGUUUGGAAAUAGAACCUCUAGGCACCCUCCUCAGUGUGGGUGGGCUGAGAGUUAAAGACAGUGUGGCUGCAGUAGCAUAGAGGCGCCUAGAAAUUCCACUUGCACCGUAGGGCAUGCUGAUACCAUCCCAAUAGCUGUUGCCCAUUGACCUCUAGUGGUGAGUUUCUAGAAUACUGGUCCAUUCAUGAGAUAUUCAAGAUUCAAGAGUAUUCUCACUUCUGGGUUAUCAGCAUAAACUGGAAUGUAGUGUCAGAGGAUACUGUGGCUUGUUUUGUUUAUGUUUUUUUUUCUUAUUCAAGAAAAAAGACCAAGGAAUAACAUUCUGUAGUUCCUAAAAAUACUGACUUUUUUCACUACUAUACAUAAAGGGAAAGUUUUAUUCUUUUAUGGAACACUUCAGCUGUACUCAUGUAUUAAAAUAGGAAUGUGAAUGCUAUAUACUCUUUUUAUAUCAAAAGUCUCAAGCACUUAUUUUUAUUCUAUGCAUUGUUUGUCUUUUACAUAAAUAAAAUGUUUAUUAGAUUGAAUAAAGCAAAAUACUCAGGUGAGCAUCCUGCCUCCUGUUCCCAUUCCUAGUAGCUAAA